AGGCCCGCUUUCUGUCAAAAUGGCAGCGCCCAGCGUGCGCGGGUAUCUCUGAAGUUGGGGUUUAAGAUUCUUGCCCGUGAGAGCGAACGAGCCUGCCGUACUUCUGAUUUUGAAACACCUGGGUCUGGGCUUCCCGGGCGAGCGGUGGAACCUGUGAGAAGUUUCUACAAUGGUGGGCUCAGCUCUCAGGAGAGGUGCCCAUGCAUAUGUCUACCUGGUGAGUAAGGCCAGUCACAUCUCCAGAGGCCAUCAGCACCAGGCCUGGGGAUCGAGGCCUCCUGCAGCAGAGUGUGCCACCCAAAGAGCUCCAGGCAGUGUGGUGGAGCUGCUGGGCAAAUCCUACCCUCAGGACGACCACAGCAACCUCACCCGGAAGGUCCUCACCAGAGUUGGCAGGAACCUGCACAACCAGCAGCAUCACCCUCUGUGGCUGAUCAAGGAGAGGGUGAAGGAGCACUUCUACAAGCAGUAUGUGGGCCGCUUUGGGACCCCGUUGUUCUCGGUCUACGACAACCUUUCUCCAGUGGUCACGACCUGGCAGAACUUUGACAGCCUGCUCAUCCCAGCUGAUCACCCCAGCAGGAAGAAGGGGGACAACUAUUACCUGAAUCGGACUCACAUGCUGAGAGCGCACACGUCUGCACACCAGUGGGACUUGCUGCACGCGGGACUGGAUGCCUUCCUGGUGGUGGGUGAUGUCUACAGGCGUGACCAGAUCGACUCCCAGCACUACCCUAUUUUCCACCAGCUGGAGGCCGUGCGGCUCUUCUCCAAGCAUGAGUUAUUUGCUGGUAUAAAGGAUGGAGAAAGCCUGCAGCUCUUUGAACAAAGUUCUCGCUCUGCGCAUAAACAAGAGACACACACCAUGGAGGCCGUGAAGCUUGUAGAGUUUGAUCUUAAGCAAACGCUUACCAGGCUCAUGGCACAUCUUUUUGGAGAUGAGCUGGAGAUAAGAUGGGUAGACUGCUACUUCCCUUUUACACAUCCUUCCUUUGAGAUGGAGAUCAACUUUCAUGGAGAAUGGCUGGAAGUUCUUGGCUGCGGGGUGAUGGAACAACAACUGGUCAAUUCAGCUGGUGCUCAAGACCGAAUCGGCUGGGCUUUUGGCCUAGGAUUAGAAAGGCUAGCCAUGAUCCUCUACGACAUCCCUGAUAUCCGUCUCUUCUGGUGUGAGGACGAGCGCUUCCUGAAGCAGUUCUGUGUAUCCAACAUUAAUCAGAAGGUGAAGUUUCAGCCUCUUAGCAAAUAUCCGGCUGUGAUCAAUGAUAUUUCAUUCUGGUUGCCCUCUGAGAAUUACGCAGAAAAUGAUUUCUAUGACUUAGUCCGAACAAUUGGAGGAGACCUGGUGGAAAAGGUUGAUCUCAUAGACAAGUUUGUACAUCCAAAGUAUAAAGUAAUUAGAGACUAAGUGACGGGGAGAGGAGACAUCAGCAACAUAAUUUUGGAAGCUGAAAAGCAGAUGGAGAAGUGGAGCAGUUAGGUUUCAGUAGACCCAAGAAAGCUGAAAUCCAAGUUGGCAGGGGAACAAUCAAGAAGCAAUCCAGCUUGAACUACAAAACCCCCCAAAAGAUUCAGGAGUUAGUAGUACAAGCUUCCUCUUGAAGUAGGGCUAACACAGGACUGUCGAUUGAAAAUGUGUUUGAGGAGCAGAACCCUCGAUUUUCUCCUCACUGACGUGUAGCAAAAGGACCACUCUGCCAAUCACCAACAGGCCUUCAUCUUGGUAGAAGUCUGGAGAUUUAUUCUCUGGAGAUGAUAAAAGCAAGGUGUUUCCACCAAAACGAGAAGUAAGCUAAGACAAGAUCCACGAAGUAAGAGUUGCAACAAAAAAAGCAAGGCAAGAACCAUCCCAAAGCCUCAGCUGCGCGGUCAUCAUCAGAGGGGGAUCUGUUCAGACUGGAGCAGAGCUGAAGGCUUCAGGGACACUUCAAGAGGAUUAAGUAAUUGCAAACCUAAUAACAACCAUUGCCUCUUCUAUUUAUUGAGUGUUCAUUGUGUGUCAGACACAGUUCUAAGCAUGUGUGUAUUAACGAUUAAAUCCUGAUAGUAGCCCUAUUAGAUGGUAGUCAUUAUCCUCCUUUUAUCAGUGAGGGAAUUGAGGCACUCAGUGCUUAAUCAUUAGUCUAAAAUGGCAUAGCUGGUUAGUGGCAAAACUGAGAUUUGAACCCAGGCUGUCCACACUCAUAGCCAGCAUACCACGCCUCACCCCCUUGACAACAGGAGAAACCAAGCUGAUGACAAGUUAACACAGCUGGGAAAGCUGGGGGAAACAGAACGUUGCACAGAGAAGAAGUCAUCUUAGUUUACUGUGGAGCUCAGUAGUGACCUGAACAGGUAACAGUGUGAAAGGGGAUCUGACAGGAGUCUCCGCAUGCCCACAUCAGGAAGAUCCGGGAGGGGCACAGGCAUGGGCAGGAGAUGUGAGGCAUGAAGGAGCUAAGUGCUUCUCUUCGGUGAUACAGAGGCAAUGCCUAAAACAAAUAACAAACCAGAAGUAGCAAGAAAAAUAGCUUGUUUAAAGCUACAGAGAGACCCACCAAAGGAACCAACUAGAAGAGUUGAAAACAGGUCUCCUGUAGGUCGUCUGGGCAGACUGUGGCAGGAUAGGGGAUGGGGGCUGCUGUCUUUCAGGAAAAGUCCUGAGAAUUAUUUGACCCUUCGAAUCUGUGCAAGUAGAACUUUGAUAAAAAUAAAAGCGAAACUUUAGAAGGGAAUAAAUACCUGGUAGUACUGUCAUGAAAUAAAUCUGUUUUAUCUUCCUAGGAACUCGGUAAAUGUUAGUUUUUCUCUUUCCUUUUUCUUUCAAAGGACAAGUUCCCAUCCCAGGCAGAAAUGAAGGCCCAGUGCGGCGCAGCCGCUGAUGGCUCACCUCUCUCAGAAUGGCCCGACUGCCCUUCAGGCCUUCAUUUCUCGCUUGCCAACUUCCAGGGAAGGACAGAAAAGCAGGGGAUUCUGUUGACAGAGACCUUUGAUGAGCGCUUGUUACCGUCCGUGGCCUUGUGGGGUGCCUGGAUUGAGGCCCAGCAAAUGGCCAGAUGUGGGGCAUAGCUAAUGUGGGUAGAGCACCUCCCGCGGCUGUGGGAAGGGACAGUGACAGUGUCUGACUGCUCCCGAGGCGCUAGCAAAGGUGCCCUCCUGGCUGCAGGUAAUGGGGGAGCUGCCCCAGACAGUCUGUAAGGCAGUGAUCGUGUCCAGGAUCCUAAGAGUUUCCUUUUAGCCACCUCCAACUAGGGCAAGAGGCCAGUAUCUUGAAAGGCAGAGUUUGGGGCUUGUGUGUAUGCAGGAGAGAGAGACAAAGUGUGUGUAUUUAUAAAGCAUGCCAUACGCCGUUUGUUCAGUGCAAUAUGCCACUUUAUUUUUAUCUCUUCUUACGUCAAAGAUAGGGAAAGCCUAUUAAUCAGUAAAUCUAAUCAUAAAUAUAUGCAUAUAUAUCUACAUUAAUAUCAAGUGUUUAUAUAUUGAUAAAUUGAUUUAAGAACGCUUUUCAUUUCUGGCAGAACCUUAGACAUUAAUGAACCUGAAUUCUCUUACUGAAGUAUCCUCUUAUUAUUUUAUAGCAGUUCUUCCUACUACAGGGUAAUUAUGAACCUGAUUUUAACAAAAAAGUACACUGAUCUACUGUAAUCUGCUCAGUAAUACAAGUGAGCUUUUCUAUGCAAACCCUAUUGCUCCAAAAAGAAUUGAAGAAAAAAUGUUUUACCAAUUCAGACCCACAAGUAUUUAUUGUGCACCUACUACAUGGAAGGCGUUGGACCAGCUGCAGUGGGUAUAAUGACGAGUAAAGCAGGCUCAGCCCUUAGCUUUUUGCAUUUUAUUUUGAAAAGGAAAAUCCUAAGAACUAAGUGACCACAAUACAAGUCUGACGAGACUGGUGUAUGAGAGGAACAAGCAGGCCCCUCCUGGGGGAUCGGAGGGGAAGACAUCUCAUUUCAGGGAUCAGGAAGAGAUAGACAUGAGUUGAGGGAUUUGCACUAUUGGAAUUAUAAAAUAACACAUCCCCAACCUUCAUUCAUUGAUUCAUUUACCCAUUCAACAAUUGUGAGUGCCUGUUACCUGUCAGAUGCUCCUCUGGACCCUGGGGAUGCACCAAAGCAAAGCUCACCUUCAUGGAGUGCAGGGAAGAGAAUAGUGGAGAAGGGCAGGCUGCAUCUUCGUGGAGUGCGGGGAAGAGGAUAGUGGAGAAGGGCAGGCUGCCUUUCCCUGCUCUGACUCUACCCUGGUUUCUGUGAACAUUCAGAAGUUUCCUACGUAAUGCUGGGCAGUCCUUGGCAGUCUUGGAGUUUGGCUGGCAUGGGUGCUGUGUGUAAGUAUAGUAUCAGUGGCACCCUGGGUUCUCUGACAGCAUCAGGACAUCACUAGUAGAGUCAGCAGUGUUUCUCAGAAGCUUCUGCCCUGACCCUUUGACCAUGGAAUCCCCAGUCACAUUAGGGCCCUACGUCCACAGAGGAGCAGCAGGAGCAGAGACCUUCUGUGGAAACCACGGCUGCCCCAUCCCAGCCGGGUCAUAGGUCAGUGUGGUCUGCUUUAAUGGGACAUAACAUCCUUUCUGGACCACCCUACUUGCCACAUCCAUGGGUUUCCUCCUGGCAGACUGUGGGGUCGGAUGCCUCUUCUCCAAUUAUCUCUGUUACAGUAUUCACUGAUAACCAUCUUAGAGGGAUUAAAUCAGAACUUACAAAUGUUUUCCUGCAGUUGAUGUUUAAAAUAUUUAUUCCAAAAAAAACAAAGAUGUUCUCAGCCUGAUACAUCCUUUGUGGAUAAUAGCUUGGACUGCAUCAAGUGCCUCUGGGGUUAGGAUACUGCCCUUCCCCUUAGGUUUAACUGAAUGUUCAACAAGGAUGAGUGUAACACCGAAAAGCAUUAAGACUCGAAGACCUGCUACUCUUCAAGGGUGGAUUCCAGGCCUUGGGAAGACUGUGUUAGGGGUAUUUACAUACUACCUGUGUAUGUCGGGAGCCCCAUACACCACUGCACCUGAGACCCCUCGGUGGGAGGUUUCAGUAUCUAUCCUGUCAGGAAGUGGUUCUCUUUUAAUUGCAGUUGACCCUUGAACAAGUUUGAACUUCACCGGCCCACUUAUACGUGGAUUUUCUUCCGCCUCUGCCACCCCUAAGACAGCAAGACCAACCUCUCCUCUUCCUCCUCCUCCUCCUUCUCAGCCUACUCAAUGUGAAGAUGACAAGGAUGAAGACCUUUAUGAUAAUCCAUUUCCACUUAGUUAAUAGUAAAUGUGUAUUUUCUUAUUUUCUUAGUAACAUUUUCUUUUCUCUAGCUUACUUGAUUGUAGCAGUAUAGUAUAUAAUACAUACGACAUACAAAAUAUGUGUUAACCAUUUGUGCUGUUGGCAAAGCUCUUGGUCAAAAGUAGGCUAUGAGUAGUUAAGUUUCAGGGGAGUCAAAGGUUACAUGUGAAUUUUUGACUGGGUGAGGGGUUGGUGGCCCCAACUCCCAUCCUGUUCGAGGGUCCACCGUAUAUGCUUUUCUCUCCUUGAGAAAAAAUUUCUAGCCAAAUUUUGUCUUCCUUAAACUCUAUAGAGCUUGAGCUUCCAGCUUGUGGUCUGAGAAACCUCUCUUUCCUUGGUGUUUGAGCAGUAAUCCUUUUUAGCAUGAUUGAUUUUUUUUUCAUUCCUUUUUGUGUCCAGGAUCCCACCUUUCACUGCACUGAGUAGCUGUACAAGUUUCACUGCCCUAACAAAUUACCACAAACAUAGUGGCUUAAAACAACACACACUGAUCAUUUUACAGCUGCAGAUCAGAUGCCUGAAAUCAGUUUCACUGGGCUGAAACGGACUUGUUGGCAGGGCUGGCACCUUCUGGAGGCUCUAGGGGAAAAUCCGUGGACUUGCCGUUUCCUGCAUCUAGCGGUCCCUGCAUCCUUUGGCUUGUGGCCCCUUCCUCACAUCUCCUCCUCUGACUCUGGCCCUCCUGCCUCCCUCUUAUAAGAAUUCCUGUGAUUAUGUUGUGUCCACCCAGACAAUACACAUCUCCCCAUUUCGUGAUUCUUAACUUAGGCAUGGUUGCACAGUCCUUUUUGCCAUGUAAGGCAAUAUUUUCUCAGGUUCCAGAGAAUUGGAGGUAGGUGUCUUUGGAGGAUCAUUCUUUUACCUACCACAGGUGCUAAUUAAACAUUUUUAAAACUCAGCUGGUUGUUUCCUUUCCCCAUCUCUGUCUCUGAGUAUUUAUGGACCAGGUUUUCAAAACACAUAACUCACUUCCCUGUUAUAAAGUAAUAAAUGUUAGAAAAUUUCUCUCAGUUCUUUAAAACAGUUGGGAAAUGAUUAAAUUGUCUUUGCAGUGAUUGUGGCUUAUUACUCUGAAAACUGGACUUGAACUCCAGGUAUGUUGGGUAUCAUCCUAGGGAACCACUAACACUCUAGAAAAACCAGUAUCGCCAUUUUUCUUGGAAACUCUCCUUUCAUCUCCAAGUACAAUGGAAGACAAGGAAGAGGACGGUCCCUGUGUUGUUGCUGUUGCCAUCAUCUUUGUUGUUGUGGAUUCUUGCCUUCUUUAUCCCCAACUCCAGAAUUCCUAUCUGUGCCAACCUGUCACUGGCUUUGCUGUGGAAGCCUUGACCUCCUCUCACACACAUCAGCUGUAGCUGGCUCCAAUAUGUCAUCUGCCACACGUAACCUAGAAUUGGAAGGUAACCAAGAACUGGAAGUGUAACCAGGUAACCUAGAAUUGGAAGUGUUUGUAGAGGAGAGGAAAUAAGCUGAGUGAGUAAUGUGCUUGAGCUCCAGGGUCCACUUCACUGUUACUUACCUUGUGAUUCUUGCCACCCCCCAGAGCACCAGAGCAGUGACAUUAAACAAACUCUUGACUCUCAACCAUGUUUCUCCUUAACCUUGUUCUUUGUUUUUUUUUUGGAGACAGAGUCUCGCUCUGUCGCCCAAGCUGGAGUGCUGUGGUACAAUCUCAGCUCACUGCAACCUCCGCCUCCCGGGUUCAAGAGGUUCUCCUGCCUCAGCCUCCUGAGUAGCUGGGACUACAGGCGCAUACUACCACACCCAGCUAAUUUUCGUUUUUAGUAGAGACAGGGUUUCACCAUGUUGGCCAGGCUGGUCUUGAACUCCUGACCUCAAGUGAUCCACCCUCCUCGGCCUCCCAAAGUGCUGGGAUUACGGGUGUGAGCCACUGUGUCCGGCCAACCUUGUUCUUUGACACAGGUGUUUUAAGCAUACAUGUGGUGUGUCCUAAUGAGAAUGAAAAUUGUGUGGGUGGCUAACCAUACCGUAUAUGUCUUAGUGCUCCAGUGAGUAUCACUUGAGUGGCUUUUGAUCUGUAUUUGACAGAUACUUUAAUAAUGUUAUACAGAUAUUUUACAGAUACUAAAAUAUUUUAUAUUUUACAUAUCCUUAUGUAAUGCAUAUAUGUAUAUACAUUGUGUAUAUAUACAUAUGUAUCACAAUAUGUGAAAAUAUAUAUAAAGGCCUUGUGAAUUCUUUUCAACUAUUAUCUCUUUAUCCCCUUUUUGUGGGAUGUGUAUUUAGAAAAAAUAAUAAUAGAAAGUACCCUUUAUUAUUGUUCAGCUUCCACCCCCCUCACAGUUCAGAAGACUGAUCCUUGUAUCUUUCAAGCUGGAAGCCUUUAUCUAAACGAGGGCCUGUGAGUUUAAAUUUCUCUGGACAAACCCAGAUGAAAGAUGGCUUGUUGAAAUGAAGGCAUCUCUUCCACUGUGCUGCACUGAUUAGAUUGACCAAUCAAGCUUAGAAUAGGAAAUGACAUGGAAGAUCAGAUGCGGGAAAUCAUUGAAAUAUUUGCCCUCCUGUUACAGGAUCACUGAAGUCCACUUAUUAUGAGACCCAGAGGUUUCCCCUCUGAAGAUGCGGGAAGGCAGUGACUAUGAAACUGGUCCUGGAAGUCUGUUGUUCUGGCAUCCUCUGCCCUGGCUAAAUGAGGUUCUGGCUUCAGAGGGGUCUUGGUUUAUAAGUGCUCCAGGGAGAUGUAUAUGCAUUUAGCUACACAAAACCUGGGCUGCAUUAACGGUUCUUAAAAGCAGAGAAUAUGAAAGGGAGGACAGAGGCAUUUUCAAAAAUUGAUGUUCAAUUUUAUAACUCUCAGUUUCCAGUAAAACUUUCCGUUAUGGUCAGUAGUUUAUAAAGGAGCAGUUCUGAGUCAUUGUUAAGAGUGGAGGCUCGCAGGCAGAUUGCCUAGAUUCAAAUUUUGGUUCUACCCCUCACCAGCCAUGUUGGUUAGAAGGUUACUCAACUUCAAUUUCCUCUUCUGUGACAUGGGGAAUAGUCAUAAAAAUGCCUUCCUCAUAAUUGUUGUGAAGAUUAGAAAUAAGAUAACAUAUUAAAAGCACUUAGAUUGGGAGGCCGAGGUGGGCGGAUCACCUGAGGUGGGGAAUUCAAGACCAGUCUGAUGAACAUGGAGGAACCCCUUCUCUACUAAAAGUACAAAGUUUGCUGGGCGUGGUGGUGCAUGUCUGUAAUCCCAGCUACUCAGGAGGCUGAGGCAGGAGAAUUGCUUGAACCCGGAAGGUGGAGUUUGUGGUGAGCCGAGAUCGUGCCAUUGCUCUCCAGCCUGAGCAACAAGAGUGAAACUCUGUCUCAAAAAAAAAAAAAAAAGAGAACUUAGAACAGUGCCUGGCACAAAAUAAUUGCUCAAUAUACAUUGGUGGUUGUUACUGUUAUUAAGUUAUUGUUAUUACUUAGCAGAGAUUGGAAGCAUUAACACAUAAUCUUUCCAAGACUUUUUAUCUCCAGUAACUAAACUCCAAAAACAUAUGGGUACUUCAAGGGGGUGACCACUGAGCUAUUCAAAUGUACCCUUCUAUUCCCAAGAGUACACCAGUGUGCACUCUAAUAUACACAAGAAUACCCUAACUACAUAAACUACAUUACAUGUCUACUCAUACAUUGCCUCUUUAAGAAAUGUAUAUGGCACAGCAUUUUAUUGUCAUAGCCAUGAUGGCAUUUAUGUUUUAUAAACUGGAGGGAAGUUAUAAGAAUUUUUCAUCAAAGAACUAAUCUUUUCUAGAAUUAGAUAGAUGGUUAGCAAAAUGUAUGACUGGAUUUCUGUCAUAGAAAUUUUCAAGGAGAUGAAUUCUAGGAGAAAUUAAGCAUCUUCCCCCCACCCCAAUAACACAAGUUAUUGGAUAAUUUUAAAUUUGUGUCAAAUGGCUUAAUAUCCUUUCCACAGACCCUGAAAAUACAAACAUUUGAUAUGUGCUCGUAUCCAAUUUCAAGUUCUGCUUAUAUUUUAUUUGAAUUACUGUCUCCUUAGCUGCCAGGCGCCCCAACACGAAUGUUGGCCCCUGCGUUUUACAAUUGUUCCUGAUAGUGCUUUGUUAUGUAUUGGGAGACUUUGAUGCCCAGUGCCCGCGUUGGACUACAGUUGUUCCUUUACCAUUCUUAGCAGUACCUCAUAUGACUUGCGGUAUGGAAGGCUUUUCAAAGUCAUAUGUGUCCCACUGGGAUUAGUGCAACUGCUUAAGCCCUGGCUGUCCCCAUCUUUUCUCUGCUUGUUCACAUGGUUAAUUAUGGAUUCAUCAAAUGUUAGAGCUGGGAAAAAGAUCUUGGAGAUCAUCUGGUGCUAUUUUCUCAUUUUCAGUCCAGAGAAACAACGCUUUUCCAGCCAAGUGUAACCCCAGUCGUUAGUGCAAGGGCUUAGUCUAGACUUUGAUUCGUUCUGUAACUACAUUAAGGGGGAUGAGAAGAGAGCUCACGUUCACUCUGCACAAGGACAAAUAAAAAAAGGCCCUGCCAUCCCUUGAGGAACUCACAGUACAGCGAAGUGACAGUCCGGUGAGCAGAUAAUUAUCUUUAAUUCUUAGCCCAUUGCUUGCUCCCCUGUACUGGUAUGCCUUUGGUAUAUACUGUUUCAGCUUCUUAUCCAUCCACAUGGUUGUAAAGUGGGGAGCUUUUGUUUUUGAUGCCUGUCUCUCCAUGUAUCCAUUCAUUUAUUUUUCUAUCUAUAAGUCAUUCAUCAAAAACCACUUAGGAAUGCCUGAGCUAUGCUGCACAACAGAGUCACUUAAAUGCUACAUACCAGUGGAGAAAAAUCAUGGUUCUUGCCUUCCAGUAAUUUAUAGUCUAGUUGAAGGAUACAAGCAUAUAAAGAACAAGGUACAAACAUGUGUUAAAGGAACUGUAAUAUAAACAUGACAAGGUACAUGGCAGACACAGUUUCAUCCUGCCUAAAUCCUCCUGAGUUGUUCACAGGUAUUUCAUGUGUUAGUUAUUCGAAGGAACUUUACAAUGCACCUCCUUCUUUGGGGCAUUUACAUUUUAAAGUAGGUUGGGAAACCCGCUUUACUACCUUCCUCUCCCUUCCCUCUUUUACUUUCUUUCUUAAGUUCGAGACUGUGUCCCACCUGUGUUAUUGCUUAGAGGAGGUGGGCCUAGCCUUGUGCUCCAUGAUGGAGUUCAAAGAGAAUGCCAUCCACCAAUCUUGCACUCUCUGGCUCACAAUCUGCUUGUCCCCUUCGUUGAUUAGUUCUUUCUUUCAUUCAUACAUUUGUUUAUUCAUAUGAAUGUCCACUGUUUACUAAGCCAGUAGUCACUGUGGAAAGCAAAGGCAGACGUGGCUGAUGUUCUCAAAGAGCAAUAGUCUAGACUAGAGGGGAAAUUAACUUUCAUGGAAUAAUCACACAUGUAGAUGUGAGUGACAGCUGAAAUAAGCAUCUGCAACUUGAUGCUUUAAGAGCAGUGAGCAGGCUGGGCGCCAUGGCUCACAGGCCCGUAAUUCCAAUACUUUGGGAGACUGAGAUUGGAGGAUAACUUGGGCCCAGGAAUUUGAGACCAGCCUGGGCAAUAUAGUGAGACCCCCAUCUCUACAAAAAAUUAAAAAAUUGGCUGGGCAUGAUUGGUGCAUGCCUUUAGUCCCAGCUACUUGGGAGGCUGAGGUGGGGGGAUCCCCUGAGCCCAGGAGGUCAAGGACUGCAGUGAGGCAUAAUCACACCACUGCACUCUGGCCCAGACAAUAGAGUGAGACCCUGUCUCAGAAAAAAAAAAAAAAAAAAAGUAACAGUGAGCAGUGGAGUCAAGGUUGAGUGUGAGGCCAGGGAGAGAAGAGCAUUAUUCAAAGCCAAGGAGCUGCCUAAGCAAAGCUCCCUGGCAGGAAAAGAAAUCUAUGGAUCAGAGCUCUGGAAAGAAGGCCAGUGUGGCUGGAAAAGUGGGGGACAUGGUGUUGAGGCUGAAACGGGGCUGAGGCCAGACCACACUGGGCCUCUUUGACCAUGUAGGGAUCUCUCACUUUACCAAGAGCAAUAGAAGCCCCUGGAAUGUUUUAAGCAAGGAAUGUCACACGAUCAGAUUUGGUUUUCAAAAACAUGACUCUGGCUGCUUUGUGGAGGGGGACUGAAAGGGAAGAGUGUGGCUGCAGAACCAGCGGGAGGCUACAGCACAGCUACACAAGCAACAAGUUGUUCCAACUGAGGUUGUGGCGAGGGGAUAGAGAUAACUCAGCAGAUCCCAAAAUAAAUAAAACCCAAAAUUUCUACAGCUUGCUACUUAGUUGAACACGAGGGAAGAGGGAUGAUGCUGAUUAUGGAACCAGAUGGAUGAUGCUGCCAUUGUUGUUAAGGACACAACUGGUUGAGAUUUAGGUUUGAACACGUUUGCCUUGAGGUUUACUGGAGGCACUGAAGUAAACGUGUUGCACAGAUAGUUUGAAACAGUCUGGAGCUUACAGGAAACACAGAGACUGGCAUAUAAAUGUGUGAGUGAUCUUCAUUGAGAAUGUAUUUGAAACUGAAGUAUGGAGAAGGUGGACUAGGAAGCAUGGAGUGAGAAGAGCAAGGGGCUUUGCAUGAAUCUUAUGGAACUAGGGCCCUUGGUGGCCAGAUAGAGGAGAGCAAAUCUGCCUGGAACGUGGGGGAGCCAGGAGUGAGGAAGAGCCAGGGUGUGUGAGUGCUGGAAGCCAGGGUAGUAGGUUUCAAGAUGGCAGGAGUAGCCAACAUCACUGAAGAGCCAAUGACAUGAUCAACAAAAAGCCAUUGCAUUUAGCAAUAGGGGUCACUGGUGACUGUGGGGAGAAAUGAUCACUCAGGGGGCCAGAAGCAAGAUUAGAUAGAGUGGGUUGAAAAUGAAGUGGGAGGAGAAGAAAUGGAGACAGUAAGUAGACAACUGAAGAAAAGAAGAGAGACAAGGCCAUGCUUGGAAAGGUUGUGUGCAGUAAGAGAAGUUUUGUAAAAGUGUAAUAAACUUCAGAGUGUGUAAAAGUCAGGAGAAGGAUCCAGUAGAGUAGGAGAGGUAACUAUAUAAGAGAGAGAGACAGAGGAGAGAUGUUACAGUGUUCCUCAGAAGGUAAGACAUCAUGGGACCCCACACUUGGAAGAGGGUGAGCAGGGUUGACCUUAGACUGGACAAAAGGGUAUUUUACAUUGAAUGAAAAAGAAAAGGAAAAAUAUUUUCUCUUGUUUUGCUUAGAUUUCAUCUUGGGCUUAUAUUUGACAUGGAACUAGUCCACUGUAAUUUUUAUGGACUUUUUACCAUGGGUUUUCCACCUAACGUAUUUUUAAAUUCAGAAAGUUGGGGUAUUUUCAUUCUUUUUUUCUUUGUCAGCUCUUUUAUUACAAACUAUUCUAUUCAUUUGUUAUAUUUUCCCAUCCUUGCAGUGCAUUGCAGACAAUAUUAUUAUUACAGUUCUACAUGCAUGUUAUUACUUUAGUUUUGCAGGGACUUCCCCAUGAAUAGCAGAAUGUAAUUUAUGAAAUCCAACCAUCAUUCUCAAGGCACCUCUGUGCUAUAUGUUAAACUCACUAAAACAGCAAUGUGGAAAUAGUCACCCACACUGCUGACUUCCAGAGCAUCAGUCACGUUGCCGCUUGCAUUUGGAAGGAGCCUCCCCUGAUCCUUCUCUGGAUGAAGCCCUGGAGGGAGGCAUUACCUACCCAGGCCACUCCUCUUGCUGGCUUCACCGUUUGAACUAACUCAGGGACGGGUGUCUCUAGAUCCAUCCAAAUGUGUAUAAAGAGAUGAACUUCUACUUUCAGUUAAUUAUCAAAACUAUAAUUAUCUUAGAAAGUUAUGCAAAUUAGUCAAGUGUUAAGCCCUUCAUCGAGAAGCUAGCAAAGUAGAAUUGGUGUGUGCGGUGGUCAAGAGGGAAGAUUCUCAGAUCAGAUCCCCGGGUUUGAACGCUGGUCCUGCUACUUGCUGGCCGUGUGUGACCAUGGCAGGUUACAAUUUCUUUGUGCCCCAGUUUACUUCACUAUAAAGCAGACAUAAUACUCCCAAGCUCAUAUGAUCAUUGUAAGGAUUAAAUUAGUUUGCAUAAAGCUCUUGGAACAAUGCCUGAUGCAUAGUAAGUACUUAAUAAAUUCUAUGAUAGCAUCUUGGAUGCAGUGAUGGUGCUUCGGAAGCCUGUUACCUUCUGCUGCCUCCACGUGUUGCAGUUUCAUUUGGGAAACACUUAUUGUUUUAGUCACAUACAACUCUAAAAGGAGGUGAUUCUAUGUCCAGUUUUUCACAAUGUCUAAAAUAAUAUGGUUCACAGUAAUAAGAUUUUAUAGCAGGUGAAUGUUUACAUUCUCAUUUCCCAGAUAUAUAAUAAUCAGUAGCCACUCCCUUUGCAUUAAAAACAAGCCCCCCUGGCUACUGAAUGGCUCUUCAAUGUAGGGAGUAUCUUAGCCAGCUUGGCACAAAUAAAACCUCUUUCCUUUUCAGCUGUUUUAAACAUUUAGCAGUCAGAUCAGAUGAUUGAACUUUCAAAAAAAUUCUUCCCAAUAUCUGUUUGGAUGGAAUCAUUUGCCGUAAAGAUCUGGCAUUAUUCAAAGCUGCUCUGUGCUCCCUUAAUUGAAAAGCCCUGACAUUGACAUUGGACAGGGCUUGCCUUUGGGGCCACCAGCAGACAGCUUUCUUCAGUGCCUCGUAUUGUUAAUGACUCAGAGAAUGUGUUUCGAUGAGAUCAGAAGCAAUCCACUAAAGAAAAAGUGGAGAGGACUUGAGAGCUUAAAAGAGCGGAGAGGAGAGAUGUGAGAAAACCUAAAAAAAGACAAAAGUUGGUGUGGAAGAAGGGGUGGCGCGGGCUCCAUGGCAGAUUUGUCAUUCGUCCCAGUCCAGCUAUUUAGAAUCAUUUUUCCAGUGGGAAGAGAGAUGAAGAGAAAUCCUGUCCAAAAGAACAAGGAAGAUGUCUUUGAAAUGAUAUGAGGGGAGCCAGAGACAGACAUGGAGGUGAGCAGGACCAGGUCUUGCUCCUUAGAUCUCCAGGGAAGAUGUACUCAGCACUACUGUGCGCACCUGGGCUGCACUGGUGUCUUUACUGCAGGCAGAAAGGAUGGAUGCACGCUGGCCAGGGCCAUGGACUGCAGGUGCUUAAGUGGCCCCACAGUAGAUGGCUGUGUUCACAGCUCAGAUCUGUGGCCCCCCUGGCCUCCUCAGCCCCUCUGAACAGUAUCCCACUGUUAGCAGCUCUGCAGUGAAAGUGCAAUCUGAACACAAAUUAAGUGGCAGCUUUGGGGUUUUAAAGAAAAAGGAAAACUUUUUCAUUUUAGAAACAGAAAGCUUAAUGUCUCCUGUGUCAGUUCAUUCUAUGCUCCCUGAAAUGGUUUCAUCUCUAUGCUAAUUUUAUGCUGAAAAUAGGAACUCCCCUGUGCUGGAGAGGAGAGAAAGGGCUUGGAAGUCAAAGACUAUCCAAGUGGCUGAGAAUCAAGUGGACCCCCUUGACUCAUUUCCACUUAGAAAAUGCUUUCAAGGCAGCCAGUGUUACACCGAGGGUCCUGCCAGGGGAGCCGAGGCCUUUGCCUGUCACCCUGGGAGCUGGCUUCCAGGCCUUGGGCAUGGAUCCCUCGCCCAGAGUCUGCUUGGUCUUGCACCAAUGAUUUCACAGGUUAUAUCCAGACCUCAUGCUUGAUAAUAAGGUAGUAAGCUGACUUCCCUUGGUUUCCUCCACUUCUGUUUUAAAUGAAUAAUUAAUCCAUUAAAAGCAUCAUCUCAAAAGCACAAAAUAUCCUAUAAUCUAUGACUAUAAGUUCUUAGAAUAAGAAGUGGACAUUGUGUUAUGCUUACUUGUAGACUGGUCUGUCUCUCUUAGUAGGACAUGAGAUGUUGAGGAUGGAUCUCAUCCUAGUCCUAGUCCUUAAGAGCACCAACAUGGACGCUUCCUCAGCGUAGGCAUAUAACUGUGAUCUCUGAAGAUUCCUAUGGGUCUAUCAUUCAGUAGCUCAAGGGCAGCUGGACGGAGAAGAGAUUAGAAGUCUUGUUCCUGCUUCUUAACUUGUUCACAAAGAUACUUCAUUUUUAUUAUUUUGGUCCUGCCAGUUCUCUUCAUCUGGUUUCCUGUAUCCUUUCAUAUACAGUGAUGCUGAGGCAUUUUUUCAUUUGUUUGUUUUAUUUGUUGUUUUAAAGAGAAAAGGGAGUAUACUUGUUGCUUCAGGGCAAAACAAAGACCAGUGGGAAGAAAGUUAUCAAAGGUUGAUUUCAGCUCCUCACAAAGAGCUUUCUAAGGACAGGCUAUUUGUGAAGGGACUAAAUGUGUUUAAGUAGAGCUGGGCGGUCACAUGAGACCAUUGUCCUGAGGAAGCUCACCCAAAAACCCCGAUGGCCAGGAUGUUGACUGAUGGCUCACCCUGGAGAGUUGACAUCUGGAGCCUCCGCUGACAAGCAGCAUGGUCCGCUGGCAGGUGAAUAGGGGCCAUGGUUCUGCGGGCUCUCUCCAGGGGUGGCUGAGGCUGGCACUCCACAGUGCUGCUAAGCACAUGGGUCACAGCUGCAAGAAUGCUGGGGUAUGCUGACUAGGCAGGUGUGCGGAGGUCACGAUGCAGCUCCAUCUUCAAAACAGGAAGCAUUUCUCGGAGCUGUAGUCUCACAGACUCUAGAGAGAUUUGAGAGGAGACUGUCAGAGAGACACAGAGGCCUGGGUGUGUGUGGAUGAGGUGAUUUCUAACCGGUUGAUAAUAAGGUAGUAAGCUUUAUGUUUCUAUCAUAUUUAUUUCCCCCCUCAGAUCAGGUUGUCUGAGCCAGAACCACAUAUCCCAGAGCAGGCAUGUUAGUGAUCUGGGAUAGAGAGAAGGACGUUCUAAACAAUGUCUGGAAACAUAAGGGGCUGAGAUGCAUUUAGCCAUUUGAAAAGAUAAUGGAAAUUUCUUUCAACUAAUUCCUUUGAGGUUUAACUGUAUAGUAUUGCCUUUUUCAUCCUUUCACAAAACAGACCCUGGAAGGACUCAAAUUGGUAAGUGAGAAGCCAGUUACUACCAACUACUGGGCAGCUUCUUGGCAGGAGGUGAGAGCUUUCUGCUUCCUUUUUAGGACAAUUCCACCCUUCCUUGAGUGGGAGGAGUUGGUGAGGUGGCUGAAUGUCAUGAGGGUUUGGAGAGGAGGUGGCUGUAAUCGCACAGGCACUGGCAUUGAAGAGACCCCGGGAAGGGAAGUACCUCUGGCUCCAUGGCAGGAUCUGGAGGGAGGAAGGGAAGAUUCAUAGCAUAGCAGGUCUAGCGUACCGCACUUGAAAAGACUAUGGUAUUUAUUGGUUCAUUGAACUCAACUAAACCCAAAAUACUGGGUACCUCAUGUGUGCAGUUCUUAGUGCCAGGAAUGAUGGGCUGUGUAAGGAAGAAUCCAGUAACUCCCUCAACUAACUUAGAAUAUUUAUUUCCUAACUAAAAGAAACAUAAGUAAGAGUCAACAAUAUUGUUUGUUUUGCUUUUUAUGUAGUGUCAGGCACAGAAAUAUGCUCAGUAAACACUUGCUGGUUAAUGGCCACUGCAGGUCCCUGAAUUUGCGUUGAGUUGAAAGAAAUGCCACCAACCUGCCCCUCCACUGCCAGGAGUUCAAGUCAGGAGAGCAGCCAGCCUGACUAUAGAAGAACUACACAGUGCCUAAAGUUCCAGGAAACCUUCCAGUUGCAAGGAGAGAGAGCAGUGCUAUUUUAAUAAAUAGUACAUGAUAGUUUUGCUGUAUACCAGGCCUACACAGUGCUAGACACUGGAGGCAAAGACAGACAAACAGACAAAAUAAUUAAAAUGUGGUUAAGAUCAUAUCCAAAUGUAAAUUAGGUCCACCACUGUGGAAAACAGUGUGGCAGUUCCUCAAAGACCUAAAAACAGAACUAACAUUUGACCCAGCAAUCCCAUUGCUGGAUAUACACCCAAAGGAAUAUAAAUUGUUCUAUUAUAAAGACACAUGCACAUGUGUAUUCGUUGCUAUUCAAAAUAGCAAAGACAUGGAAUCAACCUAAAGGAUCAUCAAUGGUAGACGAGAUAAAGAAAAUGUGGUACAUAUGCACCGUGGAAUACUAUGCAACCAUACAAAAGAAUGCGAUCAUGUCCUUUGCAGAAACAUGGACAGAGCUGGAGGACAUUAUCCUUAGCAAACUAACACAGGAAGAGAAAACCGAAUAUUGAAUGUUCUCACGUACAAGUGGGAGCUAAAUGUUGCAAACACAUGGACACAUACUGGGGCCUAUCGGAGGGUGGAGGGUGGGAAGAGGGAGAAGAUCAGGAAAAAUAACUAAUGGGUACUAGGCUUAAUACCUGGGUGACAAUAUAAUCUGAAUACCAAACCCCCAUGACACAAGUUUCCCUAUAUGACAAACUUGCAUAUGUACCCCUGAACUUAAAAUAAAAAUUAAAAAAUAAAAAUAAAGAUUAAAUUUGGCUGGGCACAGUGGCUCACGCCUGUAAUCCCAGCCCUUUGGGGGGCCAAGGUGGGCAGAUCACAAGGUCAGGAGUUCGAGACCAGCCUGGCCAAUAUGGAGAAACCCCAUCGCUACUAAAAAUACGAAAAUUAGCCUGGUGUGGUGGUGCAUGCCUAAAGUCCCAGCUGCUCAGGAGGCUGAGGCAGGAGAAUCGCUUGAACCCAGGAGGUGGAGGCUGCAAUGAGCCGAGAUCACGCCACUGCACUCCAGCCUGGGCAACACAGCAAGACACCGUCUCAAGAAAAAAAAAAAAAGAUUAUAUUCUUUGUUGAAUAUAACAAAGUGAAUAUAAACAAAAUGAAAAUUUGGGGGAAAAGUAAAAUAUCAUUUGGCAUUAAAGAUAACCCCUUAAGAAAAUCACUAUCAGUACCAAACAUGGAGCCAUCCAGCCAAACCCAUAGAAUUCUAGAACAUCAGAGCUGGAUAAGCCCUUAGAACAAUCUGUCCAAAUCUGUUAUUUUGCAGAGGGGGAAGUGGAGACCCAGCCAUGCAAAGGUAUUAGCAACAGUUAGUUUACAUUUCUUUCUGGCUGCAUUUACAGUGGGUAAAUACAUCUUAACUUUAGUGGGUUGAAAAAGACAGGUGCUAUUUCCUCAAACAAUAUUUUGGCUGCUGGUGAUCGACUCUUAGAGCAAGAGAAACACUUUCUAACAUCGAUGUGGGAUUUUGUGUGUGAUGUGUGGGUUUCCUGAGCUGCUGAGCUUUUCCACAAUCUCCUGCUCUAUUACUUCGUAGCCCACUUUCCUUUAAUACCCACCGUCAGAGAGGUUCUCUUUACCAUUCCUCUGCUCAGCUCCUUCAGAAGUCUGUGUACACCGACAAUAAAUGGUAGGUCUGAAAACAGAUGAGAGGUUUUUAAAUUUGAAAACAGAUGAGAGGCUUUCUUCCCUCAAGGGAUGAUGUGGGGUUUAGUAGCUUCAGCUAUGUUGAAUUUUACUUAUAAAUGGUGAUGACUUGCUUAUAAUGUGAGGUUUAUUUUCUGUUUUAUAUGUAUCUUAUAAGCAGCCACAUGAGCAAAUAUUUAAUUUAUUGUCACUCUUGUACUGUUGGACAGCAGCAGCUCAUGUGAAUGAUACUAUACCAAUUCAAGCUCGGGAAUGACUAUUGGACACCCAGCACACUGUUAGGGUUAUCUGCGUGUGUCCAUGUGAUACUGAAAUGGCUGGUCCCCUGGUCAAAUAGCCAGAGAAACCAGAGGGAAAGUGAAUUCCUGAACUUCAUUCAAUUAAAUGAAUUGAGGUUUAGAUGUUUUUUACUGUUUAAUUCAGGCGAAACAUUUGUUAUUCUUUAUGUAGAAACAGCUGAGGCAAAAAUGGAUGGCUUAGAAGGAAUAUCCAAGUUUGAAUCCAGGUUUUACCUCUUCAUUGCUAUGUUACCUUGAGCAAGUUUCUUUUUUGUGUGUUUGGGUUUUUUUUUUUUUUUUUUUUUUUUGAGAUGGAGUUUGUCUCUUGUUGCCCAGGCUGGAGUGCAAUGACGUGAUCUCGACUCACUGCAACCUUCGCCUUCUGUGUUCAAGUGAUUUUCCUGCCUCAGCUUCCCGAGGAGCUGAGAUUACAGGCACCCACCAUCACGCCCUGCUAAUUUUUUUUGUAUUUUUAUAGAGACGGGGUUUCACCAUGUUGGCCAGGCUGGUCUCGAACUCCUGACCUCAGGCGAUGGACCCGCCUUGGCCUCCCAAAGUGCUGGGAUUACAGGCAUGAGCCACCACACCCAGCCCACGUUGAGCAAGUUUCUUAACUUCUCUAGGCCUCAAGGGCUUUAACCACUUGUAAUGAUGAUAAUAGUGCACAGUGCUUUCAAGGUUAUAUUUUAAUAAUCAAUAUAAGGUACCUAGUGCAGUCCCUGAAAAAACAAACAGAUGUUAAUUCCCUUUCUCCUAAGAAAGUAGUCCUGGAAUGGGAAAAUAGGAGCCAUUCCUUGACACGGAGCAGACGUGUUAUCCUGGCCUCCUAUGCCAUUGCCUUCUGUGGUCAGUACUUGAACAUUGUGCCCUCGGAUUCCAUCAACAGAUCCUGAGAAACAGAGAAAGUUGCUCCCGCAGGUCCCAUAGUAAGCUUGUUGAGUGUUGUCCAUUCCUAUCACUCAGCCCACCUCCCCCCACCCCCCCGCUGCCUAUAAAACCUUUUGUGGGAAAUGUUUUAAAAAUUAAGCACCAAGGGUUAGUGUGCCUCAAGAUAAGGGUAAAUUUGACCUUAAGGGUUUUGUAAGUGACCAUUUUUCCUUCACUGUGGCUGGGGAGAGCCACCGUAUACGUCAGCCCCCAGGGCUUGCUGUUGUGUUGCUCUUUUCCCUGAUCUCAGUAGUCCUGUACUUGCUAAUAUUUUCGCUCAUCAUAUUGCAGUGUAUUAGGAGAGGGCUCUGAUGCUGUUCUGUGGUAUUAUAGGCCCAAGUCAAGAGCUCCCAAAUCCUGCCCUGCUAGUCAUUUGGCCUCCUGAUGGCAAACAGAGGUCCUGAGAUUCGGAGAGUGAAGCGGAGUGGCUGCCGGCACCACCUUCUCACCUGCAAGAGCACCCAGAGCCUUGUCCGGAGUUGGGCUUAUUGGAGGAGCUGGUGAAGGAGAAGAGGCUGAGUUGGCUUAAGCACCCCUUCUGCCUGCCUCUAACCCCACACCUUCAGAUCCCUUUAGCUGCUUGCACAGCUCAUGACCUAUGAACGGGGGUGGGGAAGAAGUAGGCAGAAUGGAGUCUGACAUGAGAAAAGUGUCAAUAACAUCCCAUUUCUUGUGUUGAUUCUUGAUUUCUGUUCAUAUUCAAACAUUAUUUUGUUGUAUAUUUUCUUUCGUAGGCCUCCUUAAAAUUCUCGUAGAAUGAGGCAAGAUAUAAACACUUACAUAGAAGUUAACAGCAGUGUGUUAAUGAUAUAUGCAGCCAAGCAUAGGCGCUUAUGCCCAGAGUGCGCAAGUAUACAGAGGACAUUCAGUGGCCAAAGUUGGCUAGAGUUGCUUUGGUCCUUGAUCAAGUCCUGUUUAGAUUUCUCCACCCAAAUAAGUUACAUCAAUACUGACUAGAUAAUACAUAUUCAACAGGCAGUACACCCCCUGAUCAUUGUGGAUAUCACAAUUCAGGAAAUCAUUUACUUACUAAACAUUUUUACUUACUAAACAUUUACUUACUAAACUUUUGUGUCCCCUACUAAACUUUUAGCUUCUAGAGAGUAGAAACCAUGUCCUGUUGUUCUUUAUGCUUAUAGUACUUGGCCCACAACUGAUGCACAAUGGAUCACGAGGGGUGACUAGAUAAAUGAGAAUUUUUUAAUGGCAAGAUGAUUCAGAGCAAAUGAAAUGUAGAAUAUCAUAAUAUUUUAUAAGGAAUGGCAUUUUGGGCAAGUUAUUACUUGUACGUACUUUUAGAAACAGUCUCUUCCUCUAACCAAAUGCUUCUGAGUAGGAUCCUGCUUUAAUGGAUAGAAAAACAUGAGUUCUCAUUAGUAUGCACAGCACUGAAGCCCAGUUACAUUUUUUUUUUAAAUAAGCACACUUUUUAAGUGCUGCCAUGCAGUGUCAUCGCUCCAAAAGCUUAUCACAUUGUUCAUUUUCUUAGCAGGCUCAGUUCUACUGAUGGUGUAAAGUUUCAACCGGGGCUCUUCAUAAUUAUUACGAAUUCUUAAGACUGAAAUCAGGUGGCUUUUUAUUUUUAGUGUCCUUAUUGUGCUCACUCAAGACUAUAUAUUCAGCAGUGUGCAGUCUAUGCCUGACUGUAUAAAAGACUGGAAUGUUCACACACUAUAAUGAAUAAUGAGUGUCAGUGAACUCAUUACAGUAAAUCCUUAGGUAAUUACUUUCUGCCUUAGUUGGGGGACUUAUGGUAGCAUAAGCUAAAAUUAUUUCAUCUCCAGACAAACCCUGAGGUGGCUGUUGGAGUUAAAUAUAAUUCAUUUGCAGCAUGUUUAUUAUAGUUAAAUUUAACUAAUUUAGGGCCUGUUGCUGGCCAGAAGCUGAGGAGGAGGAAGUUGCAGUGUCCAUGAGUACCUCAGAAAAAUGAGGCUUCAUGGCCGAGCUUUCAGAGCAUGACGUAAGAGUUACUCCCACUCUGUCUCUGCUCUUCCUGUCCCCAGAGCUGGAUGGGUUUGUUCAUGAAAGUGAUUGGCUAAUGAGCUCUUCAGGCAUAGGAUUAAUGUGGUGUAGCAAGAGGAAGUCUCAGCGUUGAGCUGGGGCUCUGCUCAGUUCUCUCCUCUGUUUCUGCCGGAACUUCCUGGUGUUACAGAAAGAACUAUGGUGUUCAAGGUCACUGUUGUAUGAAUGGAUUUAUCAGCAGAUGGUGAGGCUCCCCCUUCUCGUGCCCCAUUUCCACUCAACACUGUCGGGCCAGUCUGGGCGUUAUUUCUUCCUAAGCCUUCCAGCCUGGAAGACUUAGCUCUGGAAAAAAUAGGAAAGGACUUACUCCAAGAACCAAGCACAUGUUUACAGAGGAUGGUUUAACCUUUAAAGAUGUUGCCACUGAAGAGUUUUUAGAUUAGAUUUUGCCUCAUGAGAGCUCUUCUGAGCUGGAUGGCUUGCUCUACCAAAGAUGUUACAGGGACACCCGCAGGAGAAAUCGCAUCAACGCGGGGAGGUGAGGCUUCUGAGCCAUCGCUUGUGUCUAAGAACAUAAGCCAAAAAUCACUGUAGGGGGACUGUUCCCCAGAAGACAGGGACCUUGCCAGGAGAGGAAACACAAUUCCGAUCAUCGUGAGGAACGUGCAUUUGCGGAAGACAUUGUCCUACUUUUCCACAAAAAUACCAUGUCUCCAUUCUGGAAAUAUGUGCACUGUGCUAAUUGCUCAAGAGAAGGUAGCAGUUGGAAAAAGUCCAGAGAAGGAUGAGUAGAUGAACACAGGAAUCAGUCGGUAGCCGUGGGAACAGCAAAGCCCCUUCAGUGGGAAGGCAAGAGUAAAGAGAAGACAGCACUGAAGUCUGUGGAAUCUAAAGCGGCUUUGGUGGGGUUUCCUCACCGACCCAAAGUGCAGAGCUAGCAGGGUAGGCACACCCACCCGUGCCUGUGGUGGCCCGCCCUAAGACUCUAUCCAGGACAGCCACCUCAGCCUCACUAUCCCCUGGCCACGUCCUGGCCGUUCAGUCCCACCGUGACGCAGCUUACAAGCUGCAGAACCGUCUGCCUCUCAAGCCAGUGUUCCUCCCACUGUACCACAGUUGCUUCCGUUGGGUCCAGACUCUUCUGAAAACUCCCCUUUUCAAUUUUACUCAAACAGAUUUUGGCCAUGGAAAUGGUUUGUGACUUUAACGGGCAAGCUGUGAUAUAAAAAGUAAACCAUGGGUUACAUAACUUCAGGGGCAGGUUAACUUUUCCAGAAUUCUGGUCUCAAAGUAAAGAUUUAGAUUUAGUUGAGGCUAUAAAAAUUCAGGAAAAAAUAAUAAAGCAUUUCUACACCUCCCUCCUUCCCCUUGCGAGCCCCCCUUAAAAAUAGCAUCUGAAGUUUCAUUGUAGCUGAGUCACUGCUUGGUGCGAUCUAGGGCUAGGCUGCAACUGGACCUGUCAGAAUGAGGCCACAGUGAUUCAUGAUGAAGCUAAGUUUGGUUGCCACUGACAACAUGUGUUCCUCUCUGUUCUUUCCCUGGAGUUUGGAGACACUGUAUUUUGCCUUUGGAUUAGAAACGCCUUUGAGUGGUGAGAGUAAUGGGAUGAGAUGGGCCACUGCAAUUAAAGAGCCCUCUGGGCCCUCUUUCUGUGACACCCUAGCCAUUUGUUAGGGGAAGGUAGGAGUAAUUAACAUAACCAAAGACCUUUGGGGCUGUGAAGGGAAUUUAUCUCCUCUGCCUUUGCAGUUUAGCAUCAAGUCAGUCUACCAACCAAGAGCCCCCCAACACCUUUUCUGGGCCCCAAACUGUGCUUCCCAUUGAGGAAAGGCAAAUGAUAGAAUAUGCGGUCCCUACCCUGAAGGAAUUUGGGGAAGCACAAACCAAUUAGAGAAGCACUGUCUACUUCCCACGUUGAUUAUAAUCAUGUAUGUGUCAGUUUCCACGUUUGCGCCUGGAGGGCAGAAGCCACAGCUGGUUUUGCUGUGCAUGGCACCUGUGUUCCUGGAGCUGAAGUGAAUGGGUCCUGCCUCCAGCACCUGCUUCCCCACUUCUGCCAUCAGAAAGACUCGUUCGGGAAAACAUUCCUUCAUUCCCUUCCUAGGGCACCACAGUUAAUAAGGCCACAAAUUUGGGCCUGUCCAUCCUGGUGCAAGUAUCUGAGGAAGCAAGAAGAGAUCCGGGUUAGCAAGGAUACGAUUACAAUGCUUUUAUUUUUUUAAUGGGACUUGGGCGGUGAGGAAAUUCUAUGUUCCCCGUCAUUUAUGCAGACUCCAGCUAAACGUAUGCUAGUUGAACUCAUGCCAGCUCUGUGGAAGUGAGGGACAGAUACAAGAAACAUGGGAACUUUCCAAGAAAUGAAGCUUCUUUGCUGCCAUGUCGAUGAUGCUUGUUUCUGAGAAACUCAAAUGUAUGGAAGUGUAGAGUAGAGCUUCCCAAACAGGGUGCCGUAGUUCACAGAUUUGCACACAGGGGUGCCAGCAUAAUGAUCUCUGCAGCUCUUGGCACACCUUGGUAUGUCUGGAGUAUGAGAUGGACUUAACAUAUGAAUAUACAUAUAAAUAUAUAUAAUGUAUCUGUACAUCUUAGGGACUAGACAAACAAGGUGUUAAAUGUGUUCCUCUCUGGAUGGUAGGUUUAUGGAAUCCUUUAAUCAUUUUACUUAUUUGCUUAUUUAAACUUCUGAAUCUGUAACAAUUUAUUGUGUGUGUGGAAGAAUUCUUUCAGCCCAACCAAAUACUAGCCAAAAUAUUGAAGUGGAAGGUAUCAGUGUUCGGUGAUCCAGCCAAAGGUUUAUGUAUAUGUUUUAUUCAAACACUGUCUUAGAAACCAUUUGCCCUGAGGAUGUGUCCUCUAUUUUGUCAGUUUAAAAAGGAUUCUUUUCAGUUAGUGCAUUCUCAUUAAAAAAAAAAAAAAAAAAAAAGGAAAGAAAAAGAAACAGUAAAGCAGAUGUCACAUAUCAGAGAAAUUGCCACAUCUUGAUAGAUUCACACCAUUUAUUUUCUUUGCCUGUAAGCCUAAUACUGGCAACAGCCCAAACUGCCAACUUUCUUCAUUUAUUGACAUUCUUAAAAAGUUAACUUCCUGUCGAGGAUGUUUUUGACAGGGAUAUUAAGAGAAAGACUUGUUGGUCAGAUGUAGGUUCCAGCUGGCCACACUGUAAAGGCCACUGGGAAUCGGAACCUUGGCAGAUCCAUGCAGAGGUAAUAGUUUGGAAGUUGGGAAUUCUUAUUUCCCGGCAACUGUAGACAAGGAGCAAUGAUUUGCUAUUUGUAUUUUAUAUCGUAUUACAUUUGCAAAAUGUUUGUGGUCAUUCAAAUUUGUUUUUUUUCACAGUACUUCUGUGAAUGCCUGAUUUCUCUUUGCCUAGGCUCUCAGAUUCUUGAGGGGGUGGAUGGAGGUGUGAUAUUUGCCUUCUUCUCACAUAGGAAUGCCUAUAACCUAAAUGAGAUCAAUAUCAUUUCGUUCUUCUGGGAGCAGUACUAUUUUUGCCAGUUACCAACAUUAUAAAAUACUUCCAUAUUUGGAACUGUGGCAUUUUGUACUUGGAGGGAUUUUUUAAAGAAAUUGCCUGGUCUAGUUCCUUCAUUAUACAAAUGAAACCAUUGAGACCGAACAGGCAAAGGGAAGUUCUCAGAGUCACAAGAAGUGGUCAGUGGCCAGGCUGAGGCCAGACUGUAGUUUCCUUUUUACUACUGGUCAUACUCUGUGCUUUCUACCAAUAUUUCCCAAUUACUAUGGGGAAUUAAUAAAAAAUGUUUUUUAAUCUGCAUUUUUUGGGGGAAAGAUAAAAAUACAGAGUUUGUCACAACAUAGGUGGUCAAUAAAUAUUUGGUGAAGAA